AGGCUGGAGGCCCGCGGGCAGUGGAGAGACGCUGGGGAAGGGGGGUCCUGACAGGGGAGCCCCGCCCCCACCCCAGGCGACUUGGCCAGCGGCCACCCGGAGCAACGCACCUUAGGGUGGAAGGACGCUUCCCACUGACCACGUCUCCCAUCCCCACCCAGAGCCUCCCGUUCGGUAUUUUGGGAAGAAGCCACAGCAUCUUCCUUUACGUCCACUUUAAUUGAGCAUCUAGGAUGUGUGGGCGAGGCAGUCUCACAAGCAACGUGAGAGAAGCUCGGGUAGAGGUUCGAAGAGCUGGGAGCGCAGGGCGGGGACCUCGCACGGGAGGGUGCGGGCGGGAGCCUGCCUCGCGAGCCCGGGCCACGGCGGCUGCUCCCGACCGUGACUGGGACCCGGGCAGGGAAGGUCGCUACAAAGCCUGCCGGGCGAACCGAAGGCAGCUUUGUGCGGAGCCAUGCCAGGAAGCUUGGGAACCGUGAGCCACAAGAGGGAAAAUCUGUGCAUACAGUGUGGACAUCUAAGUCAUACAUAACAAGCCUAUCGCAUCCUUGGAGCAUGGCACAGCAGGAAUAAAGGAGAAAGAAGCUGGAAUCAGACAGUGGGGGUCAGGGAGAAGAUCUAUAACAUUCUGCUAGGUGGAUGAGAGAUUCAAAGGAGAUGACAUGAUCUGUGAAGGAAAUUGCACUGGGCAGGUGUCAGCUCAGGCUGCUGUCCACAUGAUGCCUGGGACAUGUCUGAGGGACUAGCCUGCUGCAAGUUAACAGCACAUAAUUCUGGAAGGGCGGUGGGAAACCCUGAGCCAGAAGUGGUUCUUAUUUUCGCUCAUGUGUGUGCAGUGAGUAUUUAGAGCAUAGGAUAUUGUGCUGCCCCUGAACCUUAUGACUUCCCAGAGGUGACCAACGUUUUAGCUAAAAACAUUUAGCUAAAUGUUUGAAUGGAAUUGUGCUUUAAAAUAAGGUACAACUUGCUGAGCAUGGUGGUGCAUGACUACAGUCCCAGCUACUCGGGAGGCUGAGGAGAAAGGCCCAGGAAUUCAAGUCCAGCCUGGGCAACAUAGCAAGACACGUCUCUACAUAAUAAUAAUAAUAAUUAAUACAUAAAAUAAGGUACAAGAUGCUGGGGGUAAAGAGAGAAGAGGAGGGGCAUCAUGUCAAGCCUCUCCAGGAGAAAGGACACACCUGCUGGAUUGUGUGAGGGAUUUAGAAUAGGGGCAUAUAAGGGAACACAGGGCAGUCAAUAAUUCUACACAGGCAGCAAAUUUGAUGCUGAAGGAUGACCAAUGUGGAUGCCAUGCCACUUAACGCUACUGUUGCAGCCGCAGAUCCUAGUAUUUGAAAUAUGCCUCAAGAAGGAAACACUUAAGAAGUGCUGAAUAAGAAUUCCAAUCCUGGCUUCAUCGCUAACUUGCUUUGGGAACUUGGGCUUUAAUUUGCUCAAAGCCUCAGUUUGCUCAUCUGUAAAUUGGGGCAAAUAACAUCUGUUCAACUUACCUACCAGAAAUGUUGUGUGGCUAAAAAGAAAUAGAAGAUAUGAAAAUGCUUUGGCUAUAUUCAAAGUUCUAUAUACAUGGAAGAUAUUCAGGAUCCUCCCACCUUCAAAGUUCAUAUCUAAGAAAACCCCUACUAAAUCCUUUAGAAUGGAACUGCUCAAUAUAGUAGCCACUAGCCACAUUGACUACUGAGUACUUAAAUGUGACUAGUGCAACUGAGGAACUGAAUUUUUAAUUUUAUUUAACUGUAACUAAUUUUAAUUGAAAAACUGAUACUCUAUUCAAUUACUGGAAAACUUUUAAGUACAUUUGGACCAACCUGGACUCGUGAAUUUACUUUUGUUCCCAGUGUUUUUUUCUAUUUUUUUAUUGAUAACAUAAUAGAUAUACAUAUUUUGAGUGUGUAUUCAAACAUUUAAUAUUAAUACAUUCAUAUAAUUUGUAAAGAUCAAAUCAGUGUAACUGGGAUAUCCAUUACCUUAAAUGAAUCUACUUUUUAAAUGGUAUUUAUAAAAUCUAAAUAUAUGUGAAGUGUUUCUGCUUAAAUUUAGUGUUUGAAUUGAGAUGUGCUCCAAGUGUACAACACACACCAAAUUUCAAAGACUUAGUUAAAAAAAAAACACUGGGAAGGGCAGGAGGAAGGGAGAGAUAGGGAGAGAUUUGUUAAAGGAUAUAAAAUUAUAGCUAGAUAGGAGGAAUAGGUUCUAGUGUAGUAUGGCCAUAGUUAACAAUAAUAUAUAGCUUCAAAGAGCUAGAAGGAGGAUAUUGAAUGUUUCCAACAUAAGCAUCAAUAUUUGAGAUUAUAGAUAUGCUAAUUACAGUGUUCUGAUCACUAUACAUUGUAUAUUGAAACAUCAAUAUGUACCCCAUGAAUAUGUACAAUUAUUACAUGAAUAUGUAUCAAAACAAAUUAAAUUUAAAGACAAAACAAAGAACAUAAAACAUCUUCUUAAUAAUGUUUUAUAUUAUGUGUUGAAAUGAUAACAUCUUGUAUAUAUUGGGUAAAGUAAAAUAUAUCAUUAAGAUAAAUUUUACCUCUUUGUACUUUUUUCUUAAUGUGGCUACUAGAAAAUUUUAAAUUAUAGCCAGGUGUAGUGAUGUGCACCUGUAAUCUCAGCUACUCAGGAGGCUGAGACGGGAGGAUCGCCUGAACCUUGAAGUUCACGGCUGCAGUGAGCUGUGAUCACGCCACUGCACUCCAGCCUGAGUAACAGAGCAAGACCCUGUCUCUUUAAAAAAAAAAAAAAGUAAAAUUGGCCGGAUGAGGUGGCUCACGCCUGUAAUCCCAGCACUUUGGGAGGCUGAGGCGGCGGAUCACCUGAGGUCAGGUGUUUGAGACCAGCCUGGCCAACAUGGCGAAACCCCAUCUCUACUAAAAAUACAAAAAUUAGCUGGGUGUAGUGGUGGGCGCCUGUAAUCCCAGCUACUCGGGAGGCUGAGGCAGGAGAAUCAUUUGAACCGGGGAGGCGGAGGUUGCAGUGAGCCGAGAUCUCAUCACUGCACUCUAGCCUGGGAGACAGAGGGAGACUCCGUCUCAAAAAAAAAAAAAAGUAAAAUUACAGGGUGGCUUGCAUUUUAUUUCUGUUGGAGAGCACCACUUUAGAAAGAGACAGUGAGCAGGGAGAUCCUUAUAUCCUUAUAGGAAAUAGGAAGAGGAGCCAUUGCAGAAAUAAAUUCUGUGAUCCCAGACAAAGUGCUGGCACCAUCUCCCGGGUUUGAGAACACACCGCAGAGAUACAGAACAGCGCAGAUUGCUGUUGAGGUCAGCUCCCAGCUCCCUGCCUCAUUCCUCUCUGAUUCCUCUUUUGUUCAGGCACAAAAACACUCCAUCCUGAAACUUUUGUCAUUAUUGCCUUGGUAGAAGAAGACCACAGUUGUUACCUGGGUUUUGAUUUGGGGACAACAGCAUUUCAAUGACUAGGAGAUUUCAGGAGAAGCUAGUGGCCAUGAAGAUUCUCAAAAUCAGCAUGAACUUUAUUUUUCACUGGUGUUCUUUCAAAGUUUGCCUUCGACUCAACGUGUGGUAGAAAUUCACCCUGAAAGCAUUUGCUCUUCUCUGGUUUUGUGUCUUUUCCUCCAGAACAGCGUUGUUUUUUGCAUGUUUUGCACUUAGCCAGAGGAAGUCUGGCGCAUCCGAGCCGGCCAGCCGAGCACAUCUGGAAGUGGUUUCUGGGGCCGCCCCUCUCUGCCAGCGCAACUCCUGGGUUCCCAGCGGCUUCGCGCAGAGGUGGAAGAAACCCGAGACGUUCCGAAGUCAACGCAAGCAAAGGGGAGUGCGGGUCGGGGAGGAAUAUUCUUUUGGAAACGUAAUAUUGGCCUUGGGGCUCUCCAGCCCUUUGGGACUUCCAAUGGGAUCUUAGAAGCAGCCGAAGCAGCGUGAGGGCGGCAGCCCAGGGCCAGCCACGAUUUGAACGCUCUGCCUUGCAGCUCUUCUGGACCGAGGAGCCCAAAGCCCUACCCUCACCAUUCACCAGAAUCUGCCUUAGGAAGCUGUUCUGAGGAUCUCCAUCCCCCCAGAAAGAACUGGCCGUUGUGGAAACCCAAGUCCUGUGGGAAGAGCAGCGUGGAGGUGGGCUGAGGUUAGAAGGUGCAGAGCGUGGAAGAAGAUUGUGAGCUGAGUAUUGGACAUCUGUUCUUGAAUAGUCCCUGGGCCUGCCAUAGGAAAGGAAGUUCUCCAGGGUUACAGUUCUUAUCCGCGUGAAUACACAUGGCUCUGUUACGAAAAAUUAAUCAGGUGCUGCUGUUCCUUCUGAUCGUGACCCUCUGUGUGAUUCUGUAUAAGAAAGUUCAUAAGGGGACUGUGCCCAAGAAUGACGCAGAUGAUGAAUCCGAGACUCCUGAAGAACUGGAAGAAGAGAUUCCUGUGGUGAUUUGUGCUGCAGCAGGGAGGAUGGGUGCCACUAUGGCUGCCAUCAAUAGCAUCUACAGCAACACUGACGCCAACAUCUUGUUCUAUGUAGUGGGACUCCGGAAUACUCUGACUCGAAUACGAAAAUGGAUUGAACAUUCCAAACUGAGAGAAAUAAACUUUAAAAUCGUGGAAUUCAACCCGAUGGUCCUCAAAGGGAAGAUCAGACCAGACUCAUCGAGGCCUGAAUUGCUCCAGCCUCUGAACUUUGUUCGAUUUUAUCUCCCUCUACUUAUCCACCAACACGAGAAAGUCAUCUAUUUGGACGAUGAUGUAAUUGUACAAGGUGAUAUCCAAGAACUGUAUGACACCACCUUGGCCCUGGGCCACGCGGCGGCUUUCUCAGAUGACUGCGAUUUGCCCUCUGCUCAGGACAUAAACAGACUCGUGGGACUUCAGAACACAUAUAUGGGCUAUCUGGACUACCGGAAGAAGGCCAUCAAGGACCUUGGCAUCAGCCCCAGCACCUGCUCUUUCAAUCCUGGUGUGAUUGUUGCCAACAUGACAGAAUGGAAGCACCAGCGCAUCACCAAGCAAUUGGAGAAAUGGAUGCAAAAGAAUGUGGAGGAAAACCUCUAUAGCAGCUCCCUGGGAGGAGGGGUGGCCACCUCCCCAAUGCUGAUUGUGUUUCAUGGGAAAUAUUCCACAAUUAACCCCCUGUGGCACAUAAGGCACCUGGGCUGGAAUCCAGAUGCCAGAUAUUCGGAGCAUUUUCUGCAGGAAGCUAAAUUACUCCACUGGAAUGGAAGACAUAAACCUUGGGACUUCCCUAGUGUUCACAACGACUUAUGGGAAAGCUGGUUUGUUCCUGACCCUGCAGGGAUAUUUAAACUCAAUCACCAUAGCUGAUAUAACUCUACCCUUAAAAUAUUCCCUGUAUAGAAAUGUGGAAUUGUCCCUUUGUAGCCAACUAUAACAUUGUUCUUUAUGAAUAUUACCUUUGAUACAUAUGAUCCACAAUAUAAAAACCAAAAACUACUGUGUGCAAAUUAUACCUUGGACCAUAUAGGCAUUGAUUAACUUCUUUAAGUACAUGUGAUAACUAUGGAAAUCAAGAUUAUGUGACUGAAAAACAUAAAGGAAGAGACCCAUCUAGAUAACAGCAAUCAACCUGCUUAAUUCUGAAUGACAAUUAUAUCCACAAAUUUUUAAAACUUCUACAUGUAUUUUUCACAUGAAGAUCUCCUUAACAGGUUGCCAACCUUUUCUUUUAUAAAACUAUUACAUUUAAAAUAUGGACGUCUGAAAAAUAAAAUAUUCAUCAUUUUUA